ACGCCACCACUGGAACCCGGGGGAAGAUGGCGGCAGCCGUUCUGAGUGGGCCCUCUGCGGGCUCCGCGGCUGGGGUUCCUGGCGGGACCGGGGGUCUCUCGGCAGUGAGCUCGGGCCCGCGGCUCCGCCUGCUGCUGCUGGAGAGUGUUUCUGGUUUGCUGCAACCUCGAACGGGGUCUGCCGUUGCUCCGGUGCAUCCCCCAAACCGCUCGGCCCCACAUUUGCCCGGGCUCAUGUGCCUAUUGCGGCUGCAUGGGUCGGUGGGCGGGGCCCAGAACCUUUCAGCUCUUGGGGCAUUGGUGAGUCUCAGUAAUGCACGUCUCAGUUCCAUCAAAACUCGGUUUGAGGGCCUGUGUCUGCUGUCCCUGCUGGUAGGGGAGAGCCCCACAGAGCUAUUCCAGCAGCACUGUGUGUCUUGGCUUCGGAGCAUUCAGCAGGUGUUACAGACCCAGGACCCGCCUGCCACAAUGGAGCUGGCCGUGGCUGUCCUGAGGGACCUCCUCCGAUAUGCAGCCCAGCUGCCUGCACUGUUCCGGGACAUCUCCAUGAACCACCUCCCUGGCCUUCUCACCUCCCUGCUGGGCCUCAGGCCAGAGUGUGAGCAGUCAGCAUUGGAAGGAAUGAAGGCUUGUAUGACCUAUUUCCCUCGGGCUUGUGGUUCUCUCAAAGGCAAGCUGGCCUCAUUUUUUCUGUCUAGGGUGGAUGCCUUGAGCCCUCAGCUCCAACAGUUGGCCUGUGAGUGUUAUUCCCGGCUGCCCUCUUUAGGGGCUGGCUUUUCCCAAGGCCUGAAGCACACCGAGAGCUGGGAGCAGGAGCUACACAGUCUGCUGGCCUCACUGCACACCCUGCUGGGGGCCCUGUACGAGGGAGCAGAGACUGCUCCUGUGCAGAAUGAAGGCCCUGGGGUGGAGAUGCUGCUGUCCUCAGAAGAUGGUGAUGCCCAUGUCCUUCUCCAGCUUCGGCAGAGGUUUUCGGGACUGGCCCGCUGCCUAGGGCUCAUGCUCAGCUCUGAGUUUGGAGCUCCCGUGUCCGUCCCUGUGCAGGAAAUCCUGGAUUUCAUCUGCCGGACCCUCAGCGUCAGUAGCAAGAAUAUUAGCUUGCAUGGAGAUGGUCCCCUGCGGCUGCUGCUGCUGCCCUCUAUCCACCUUGAGGCCUUGGACCUGCUGUCUGCACUCAUCCUCGCGUGUGGAAGCCGGCUCUUGCGCUUUGGGAUCCUGAUCGGCCGCCUGCUUCCCCAGGUCCUCAAUUCCUGGAGCAUCGGUAGAGAUUCCCUCUCUCCAGGCCAGGAGAGGCCUUACAGCACGGUUCGGACCAAGGUGUAUGCGAUAUUAGAGCUGUGGGUGCAGGUUUGUGGGGCCUCGGCGGGAAUGCUUCAGGGAGGAGCCUCUGGAGAGGCCCUGCUCACCCACCUGCUCAGCGACAUCUCCCCGCCAGCUGAUGCCCUUAAGCUGCGUAGCCCGCGGGGGAGCCCUGAUGGGAGUUUGCAGACUGGGAAGCCUAGCGCCCCCAAGAAGCUAAAGCUGGAUGUGGGGGAAGCUAUGGCCCCGCCAAGCCACCGGAAAGGGGAUAGCAAUGCCAACAGCGACGUGUGUGCGGCUGCACUCAGAGGCCUCAGCCGGACCAUCCUCAUGUGUGGGCCUCUCAUCAAGGAGGAGACUCACAGGAGACUGCAUGACCUGGUCCUCCCCCUGGUCAUGGGUGUACAGCAGGGUGAGGUCCUAGGCAGCUCCCCGUACACGAGCUCCCGCUGCCGCCGUGAACUCUACUGCCUGCUGCUGGCGCUGCUGCUGGCCCCGUCUCCUCGCUGCCCACCUCCUCUUGCCUGUGCCCUGCAAGCCUUCUCCCUCGGCCAGCGAGAAGAUAGCCUUGAGGUCUCCUCUUUCUGCUCAGAAGCACUGGUGACCUGUGCUGCUCUGACCCACCCCCGGGUUCCUCCCCUGCAGCCCAUGGGCCCCACCUGCCCCACACCUGCUCCAGUUCCCCCUCCUGAGGCCCCAUCGCCCUUCAGGGCCCCACCGUUCCAUCCUCCGGGCCCCAUGCCCUCAGUGGGCUCCAUGCCCUCAGCAGGCCCCAUGCCUUCAGCAGGCCCCAUGCCCUCAGCAGGCCCUGUGCCCUCGGCACGCCCUGGACCUCCCACCACAGCCAACCACCUAGGCCUUUCUGUCCCAGGCCUAGUGUCUGUCCCUCCCCGGCUUCUUCCUGGCCCUGAGAACCACCGGGCAGGCUCAAAUGAGGACCCCAUCCUUGCCCCUAGUGGGACUCCCCCACCUACUAUACCCCCAGAUGAAACUUUUGGGGGGAGAGUGCCCAGACCAGCCUUUGUCCACUAUGACAAGGAGGAGGCAUCUGAUGUGGAGAUCUCCUUGGAAAGUGACUCUGAUGACAGCGUGGUGAUCGUGCCCGAGGGGCUUCCCCCCCUGCCACCCCCACCACCCUCAGGUGCCACACCACCCCCUAUAGCCCCCACUGGGCCACCAACAGCCUCCCCUCCUGUGCCAGCGAAGGAGGAGCCUGAAGAACUUCCUGCAGCCCCAGGGCCUCUCCCGCCACCCCCACCUCCGCCGCCGCCUGUUCCUGGUCCUGUGACGCUCCCUCCACCCCAGUUGGUCCCUGAAGGGACUCCUGGUGGGGGAGGACCCCCAGCCCUGGAAGAGGAUUUGACAGUUAUUAAUAUCAACAGCAGUGAUGAAGAGGAGGAGGAAGAGGAAGAAGAGGAAGAAGAAGAAGAGGAAGAAGAGGAAGAGGAGGAAGACUUUGAGGAAGAGGAAGAGGAUGAAGAGGAAUAUUUUGAAGAGGAAGAAGAGGAGGAAGAAGAGUUUGAGGAAGAAUUUGAGGAAGAAGAAGGUGAGUUAGAGGAAGAAGAAGAAGAGGAGGAUGAGGAGGAGGAAGAAGAACUGGAAGAGGUGGAAGACCUGGAGUUUGGCACAGCAGGAGGGGAGGUAGAAGAAGGUGCACCUCCACCCCCAACCCUGCCUCCAGCUCUGCCUCCCCCUGAGUCUCCCCCAAAGGUGCAGCCAGAACCCGAACCUGAACCCGGGCUGCUUUUGGAAGUGGAGGAGCCAGGGACGGAGGAGGAGCGUGGGGCUGACACAGCUCCCACCCUGGCCCCUGAAGCGCUCCCCUCCCAGGGAGAGGUGGAGAGGGAAGGGGAAAGCCCUGCGGCAGGGCCCCCUCCCCAGGAGCUUGUUGAAGAAGAGCCCUCUGCUCCCCCAACCCUGUUGGAAGAGGAGACUGAGGAUGGGAGUGACAAGGUGCAGCCCCCACCAGAGACACCUGCAGAAGAAGAGAUGGAGACAGAGACAGAGGCCGAAGCUCUCCAGGAAAAGGAGCAGGAUGACACAGCUGCCAUGCUGGCCGACUUCAUCGAUUGUCCCCCUGAUGAUGAGAAGCCACCACCUCCCACAGAGCCUGACUCCUAGCCAUCUUCUGCACCCCACUCUUUGUUUCCAAUAAAGUUAUGUCCUUAGAUAGCGACUGCUGCUUCUGCCUUUUGCCACACCUGGGUCCCCAGCCAGAAGCUCAAGUGUCUGCUGGGCUUUUCAGGGUGUCCAUAGUAUUCCCCAGAUGUCUCCAUAGCUGUCCUCUUUUUGACGAUCCAGAGAGGAACAACUGACAUUGGUGUAAUGGACUGUCCCAUCACUCAGCACGAUGGUGUCAGAAUUGUAGGAUUCUGGCUGGAUGCUAAACGUGCAGAAUUGUGUGUAGGGUUAAGAAUGAGGAGUUAUAGAGACACAGCCCUGCUUUCGUGUUUGUAUUCGGGGUGGGAAAUGUGUGGAGAAUGCAUCCUAGUGAGUGGACCUGUGUCAACACCCACAUGCCCACACGCAUGCGUGCUCAGCCCCUUGGUCUGAAAGGGCAGGCUGAGUGAUUGCUCAGUCUAUGGAAGUUUAGGAAAUUAGGAAAAGGUGUGGAGCAGUUUAGUCAUUGAAUUCUGGGAAAUUUGGACCUUACCCCAAGAUGAAAGGGUGUCCGUAGUGGGUACGUUGGGAAUGACCUCUGUUUUGGGGCUAGUCCUCCUAAUGACAGUUCCCCUCACAGCUCCCUGGCAGGAGUUUGAUAAGCUCACCCCAGGCCUUCCUGCUCACUCUUGAGGUGUGGAUAUUUCCCACCCAGUGUCUUUUCUUUUCUUUUUUUUUUUGAGAUGGACUCCUGCUCUGUCGCCCAGGCUGGAGUGCAGUGGCAUGGUCUCAGCUCACUGCAACCUCUGCCUCCCAGGUUCAAGCAAUUCUCUGCCUCAGCCUCCUGAGUAGCUGGGAUUACAGGCGCCUGCCACUGCCUGGCUAAUUUUUGUAUUUUUAGUAGAGGUGGGGUUUCACCAUGUUGGCCAGGCUGGUCUUGAACUCCUGAGCUCAUGGUCCACCUGCCUUGGACUCCCAAAGUGCUGGGAUCACAAGCAUGAGACACCGCACCUGACUGUCCCAGUGUCUUUUCUUUAAGCACUAAUCCUAUUCUAGGCCUUGCUGGGAUGGACGUGUGAGGAUGAACCGAGAGAUGUGUCUGUGAGAGGGUACCAAGAUUGGUGGGCUUGAACUAGGGGCCCCGUGGUUUUUUUUGCUCAGUCAGUUGAAUCAUGAACGUAAGUAAAGUGCCUUCGCAAUGCAGAAGAGGGAGUCAUUUCUCCCAACAUGUAUCCUGAAGAGCCCUUUGAGGAGGUGGCAUUUGAGCUAAUUUUUGGAAACUUCAGUAGGAUUUUAAAAAGUUACCCCUCAACUUGUUUUCGAAAUAAACAGAAAAGUGAGAACAGUAUAAUAGAUAACCUUUGCCUAGAUUUGCCAAUUAACAUUUAGUCAUGUUAACUCUUAUCCCUAUAAACUGCGUAUCUACAUGUAGACAUGUAUCUAUAUUACACCCAUAUAUCUGUCUAAUCUAUACAUCUGUAGUUAUACACAUUUCUUUUUUCAUGGGACCACGUGAAAGUAAGCUGUAGACACCGUGGCCCUUCCCAUCCCAGAUUCUUUAACAUGAAUUAUCUUCUAAGAUAAGAAUGUUUUUCUGCACAAUCCUGAUACCAUUAUCAAACCUAAGAAAAAUAACAGUAAUCCAGUGAUAAUUGUGAUAUUAAAAUUUUCCUAUUAAUUCCUAAA